ACACACUCGGGGAGCGGGAGCGCGGCGCGGACGCAAAGCCGCCGGGCUGCUGCGCCCAGAGCCAGCCGGAGCCGGAGCCGGAGCCCGAACUGCAGCUCCAGCCCCAGCCGUGCGGAGCCGCAGCCCAGGCCGGGGCCGGCGGCGGCUCAUGGACAGCGGGGCGGGCGGCCGGCGCUGCCCGGAGGCGGCCCUCCUGAUUCUGGGGCCUCCCAGGAUGGAGCACCUGAGGCACAGCCCAGGCCCUGGGGGGCAACGGCUACUGCUGCCCUCCAUGCUGCUAGCACUGCUGCUCCUGCUGGCUCCAUCCCCAGGCCACGCCACUCGGGUAGUGUACAAGGUGCCGGAGGAACAGCCACCCAACACCCUCAUUGGGAGCCUCGCAGCCGACUAUGGUUUUCCAGAUGUGGGGCACCUGUACAAGCUAGAGGUGGGUGCCCCGUACCUUCGCGUGGAUGGCAAGACAGGUGACAUUUUCACCACCGAGACCUCCAUCGACCGUGAGGGGCUCCGUGAAUGCCAGAACCAGCUCCCUGGUGAUCCCUGCAUCCUGGAGUUUGAGGUAUCUAUCACAGACCUCGUGCAGAAUGGCAGCCCCCGGCUGCUAGAGGGCCAGAUAGAAGUACAAGACAUCAAUGACAACACACCCAACUUCGCCUCACCAGUCAUCACUCUGGCCAUCCCUGAGAACACCAACAUCGGCUCACUCUUCCCCAUCCCGCUGGCUUCAGACCGUGAUGCUGGUCCCAACGGUGUGGCAUCCUAUGAGCUGCAGGCUGGGCCUGAGGCCCAGGAGCUAUUUGGGCUGCAGGUGGCAGAGGACCAGGAGGAGAAGCAACCACAGCUCAUUGUGAUGGGCAACCUGGACCGUGAGCGCUGGGACUCCUAUGACCUCACCAUCAAGGUGCAGGAUGGCGGCAGCCCCCCACGCGCCAGCAGUGCCCUGCUGCGUGUCACCGUGCUUGACACCAAUGACAACGCCCCCAAGUUUGAGCGGCCCUCCUAUGAGGCCGAACUAUCUGAGAAUAGCCCCAUAGGCCACUCGGUCAUCCAGGUGAAGGCCAAUGACUCAGACCAAGGUGCCAAUGCAGAAAUCGAAUACACAUUCCACCAGGCGCCCGAAGUUGUGAGGCGUCUUCUUCGACUGGACAGGAACACUGGACUUAUCACUGUUCAGGGCCCGGUGGACCGUGAGGACCUAAGCACCCUGCGCUUCUCAGUGCUUGCUAAGGACCGAGGCACCAACCCCAAGAGUGCCCGUGCCCAGGUGGUUGUGACCGUGAAGGACAUGAAUGACAAUGCCCCCACCAUUGAGAUCCGGGGCAUAGGGCUAGUGACUCAUCAAGAUGGGAUGGCUAACAUCUCAGAGGAUGUGGCAGAGGAGACAGCUGUGGCCCUGGUGCAGGUGUCUGACCGAGAUGAGGGAGAGAAUGCAGCUGUCACCUGUGUGGUGGCAGGUGAUGUGCCCUUCCAGCUGCGCCAGGCCAGUGAGACAGGCAGUGACAGCAAGAAGAAGUAUUUCCUGCAGACUACCACCCCGCUAGACUACGAGAAGGUCAAAGACUACACCAUUGAGAUUGUGGCUGUGGACUCUGGCAACCCCCCACUCUCCAGCACUAACUCCCUCAAGGUGCAGGUGGUGGACGUCAAUGACAACGCACCUGUCUUCACUCAGAGUGUCACUGAGGUCGCCUUCCCGGAAAACAACAAGCCUGGUGAAGUGAUUGCUGAGAUCACUGCCAGUGAUGCUGACUCUGGCUCUAAUGCUGAGCUGGUUUACUCUCUGGAGCCUGAGCCGGCUGCUAAGGGCCUCUUCACCAUCUCACCCGAGACUGGAGAGAUCCAGGUGAAGACAUCUCUGGAUCGGGAACAGCGGGAGAGCUAUGAGUUGAAGGUGGUGGCAGCUGACCGGGGCAGUCCUAGCCUCCAGGGCACAGCCACUGUCCUUGUCAAUGUGCUGGACUGCAAUGACAAUGACCCCAAAUUUAUGCUGAGUGGCUACAACUUCUCAGUGAUGGAGAACAUGCCAGCACUGAGUCCAGUGGGCAUGGUGACUGUCAUUGAUGGAGACAAGGGGGAGAAUGCCCAGGUGCAGCUCUCAGUGGAGCAGGACAACGGUGACUUUGUUAUCCAGAAUGGCACAGGCACCAUCCUAUCCAGCCUGAGCUUUGAUCGAGAGCAACAAAGCACCUACACCUUCCAGCUGAAGGCAGUGGAUGGUGGCGUCCCACCUCGCUCAGCUUACGUUGGUGUCACCAUCAAUGUGCUGGACGAGAAUGACAACGCACCCUAUAUCACUGCCCCUUCUAACACCUCUCACAAGCUGCUGACCCCCCAGACACGUCUUGGUGAGACGGUCAGCCAGGUGGCAGCCGAGGACUUUGACUCUGGUGUCAAUGCUGAGCUGAUCUACAGCAUUGCAGGUGGCAACCCUUAUGGACUCUUCCAGAUUGGGUCACAUUCAGGUGCCAUCACCCUGGAGAAGGAGAUUGAGCGGCGCCACCAUGGGCUACACCGCCUGGUGGUGAAGGUCAGUGACCGCGGCAAGCCCCCACGCUAUGGCACAGCCUUGGUCCAUCUUUAUGUCAAUGAGACUCUGGCCAACCGCACGCUGCUGGAGACCCUCCUGGGCCACAGCCUGGACACGCCGCUGGAUAUUGACAUUGCUGGGGAUCCAGAAUAUGAGCGCUCCAAGCAGCGUGGCAACAUUCUCUUUGGUGUGGUGGCUGGUGUGGUGGCCGUGGCCUUGCUCAUCGCCCUGGCGGUUCUUGUGCGCUACUGCAGACAGCGGGAGGCCAAAAGUGGUUACCAGGCUGGUAAGAAGGAGACCAAGGACCUGUAUGCCCCCAAGCCCAGUGGCAAGGCCUCCAAGGGAAACAAAAGCAAAGGCAAGAAGAGCAAGUCCCCAAAGCCCGUGAAGCCAGUGGAGGACGAGGAUGAGGCCGGGCUGCAGAAGUCCCUCAAGUUCAACCUGAUGAGCGAUGCCCCUGGGGACAGUCCCCGCAUCCACCUGCCCCUCAACUACCCACCAGGCAGCCCUGACCUGGGCCGCCACUAUCGCUCUAACUCCCCACUGCCUUCCAUCCAGCUGCAGCCCCAGUCACCCUCAGCCUCCAAGAAGCACCAGGUGGUACAGGACCUGCCACCUGCAAACACAUUCGUGGGCACCGGGGACACCACGUCCACGGGCUCUGAGCAGUACUCCGACUACAGCUACCGCACCAACCCCCCCAAAUACCCCAGCAAGCAGUUACCUCACCGCCGCGUCACCUUCUCGGCCACCAGCCAGGCCCAGGAGCUGCAGGACCCAUCCCAGCACAGUUACUAUGACAGUGGCCUGGAGGAGUCUGAGACGCCGUCCAGCAAGUCAUCCUCAGGGCCUCGACUCGGUCCCCUGGCCCUGCCUGAGGAUCACUAUGAGCGCACCACCCCUGAUGGCAGCAUAGGAGAGAUGGAGCACCCCGAGAAUGACCUUCGCCCUUUGCCUGAUGUCGCCAUGACAGGCACAUGUACCCGGGAGUGCAGUGAGUUUGGCCACUCUGACACAUGCUGGAUGCCUGGCCAGUCAUCUCCCAGCCGCCGGACCAAGAGCAGCGCCCUCAAACUCUCCACCUUCGUGCCUUACCAGGACCGAGGAGGGCAGGAGCCUGCGGGCGCCGGCAGCCCCAGCCCCCCGGAAGACCGGAACACCAAAACGGCCCCCGUGCGCCUCCUGCCCUCCUACAGUGCCUUCUCCCACAGUAGCCAUGAUUCCUGCAAGGACUCGGCCACCUUGGAGGAAAUCCCCCUGACCCAGACCUCGGACUUCCCACCCGCAGCCACACCGGCAUCUGCCCAGACGGCCAAGCGCGAGAUCUACCUGUGAGCCCCCUACUGGCCGGCCGGCCCCCCUCCCCCAGCCGCCGGCCAGCUCCCAAAUGGCCCAUUCCAGGGCCUCACUCUCCACCCCUUCAGCGUGGACUUCCUGGCCAGGGCCCCAAGUGGGGGUAUCACUGACCUCAUGACCACGCUGGCCCUUCUCCCAUGCAGGGUCCAGGUCCUCUCCCCUCAUUUCCAUCUCCCAGCCCCCAGGGGCCCCUUCCCCUUUAUGGGGCUUCCCCCAUCUGAUGCCCAAGAGGGCUCCUCUGCAAUGACUGGGCUCCUUCCCUUGACUUCCAGGGAGCACCCCCUCGAUUUGGGCAGAUGGUGGAGUCAAGGGUGGGCAGCGUACUUCUAACUCAUUGUUUCCCUCAUGGCCGACCAGGGCGGGGAUAGCAUGCCCAAUUUUAGCCCUGAAGCAGGGCUGAACUGGGGAGCCCCUUUCCCUGGGAGCUCCCAGAGGAAACUCUUGACCACCAGUGGCUCCCUGAAGGGCUUUUGUUACCAAAGGUGGGGUAGGGACGGGGGUGGGAGUGGAGCGGAGGCCUUGUUUUCCCGUGCUGCUCCUGGACUGGCCCACCUGCCUGCCACAUGCCCACGCCUAGUCCCAUCUGGGCCCCCAUUCCCUGCUGGUCAUGCAGUGUCUGUAUAUAAGGACCUUGGAAUGACGUCCCCAUUUCUGCCUGAUUUGCAACUUUUCUUGUUGAUGUCGUGUUGUCUUGGGGGACCCCUCUGGGGGGGGACCUGCCCUGUGCCCCCUCCUCCCUGCCGCAGUGCCCCCCAACCCAGGCCUCUAUUGUUCCAUGUUGUAAAUACCCCUGGGGCCAUGGUGGGAUGGGGGUGCAGGCCAGGGAAACAACGGGUGGGUGGGGGUGGGGACGGGGGUAACAUUUGCCUAUCAGCAGAGCUGGGCUUUUAUUUAAUUUUUCUUAAAAAUACAAAUCUCUAUUUUUUUGGAA